GCAGGAAACACAGCAGUGGAGAGCAAGACACCAGCACGCUGCCCUCACCACCUCUCCUCACCACGGUGGAGGAUGUGAACCAGGAUAACAAAACCAAAACGUGGCCACCCAAAGCACCCUGGCAGCACCCUUCCCCGCUUCCCAGCACGCUGCCCAGCCCCAGCGCACCACUCUAUGCAGUCACCAGCCCUGGCAGCCAGUGGAACGACACCAUGCAGAUGCUGCAGUCCCCAGUGUGGGCCGCAACCAACGACUGCAGUGCCGCUGCCUUCUCCUAUGUGCAGACCCCACCCCAGCCCCCACCCCCACCAGCACACAAGGCAGCACCCAAGGGCUUCAAGGCCUUCCCUGGGAAGGGUGAGCGCAGGCCAGCCUAUCUGCCCCAGUACUGACCCCAGGCCAGCCAGCCUGCCUGCCUGCCUGCCUGCCCGCCCAGAGCUGUGGGGAUGAGUGUCCCCACCCCAGGGCCACUUAGCUGACACCAGCCCCUCAGAGGACCAGUGCGCCCCAUCCCAGGGAGGGUUCCUUGGGGACAAGGGUGGUUGGCAGCUCCAAGCCUUUAAACCUGGCUUCUGAAACGAUGGCAUCAGAGCCCUGGAGAGCCAGCUGGAGACACAGGCGUCUGGCCUUCAGGGGCUUGCUAGGGAACCUGCAUGCCUAGUAAGCGCCACAGGUGACUCUGAUGCAGGCGCCACAGCCACACUUGAAGAAACACAGCUCUUGGGUUUUUAGUCCUGCUGUGUGUUGGGAAGACAUCAGGCCUGAAAGCUGAGGGCAUAACUGACCAUUUUUUGGAAACCCUCUCCUCCCUCCUCCACACCUUGAGUGAUGACCACACCAAUCACUGUAUUUUAUAGCUUUUUUUUUCAUGUAGGUUUUUAGUUAAAACAUCUCCUGCCUAAAAUGCAUUGAAUAUUUUAAGAUAACAGAUAUACUGGCUGGAGGUUUGUUUAACACUAUCUAUAUUUAAGCUUAUACAAAAUGGGCAAAAUAUAGAAUAUUUGUGAUUGGAAGCAGUCACCUGGGGUUUCUGGGGGUGGACAGUUCCUCGCCACCCAGCAGCACCCUGGGACUGCGGCCUUUCCCAGCUUUAUUGAAGCAGAAUGGUGGAACUUGUGCCGGAGGUACACUGCUGAAGGUGCGUGGCGGUGGACCAGCCAGCUGCUGUCCAUGUGCAGAGCAAGGCUGCACCUGCUGCCCUUCGAUCCUUCCACACAUGGCCAGGACACUGCCACAAUCCUCGGGGUGUGGUCAAGGGGCACUCAGAGACACCUGCACUAGAAAUUGCAUUGACAUUGUGAGCUGGCUCAGAAGACAAACCAAUUAAGAUGUAGAUAGAAAUUAAUUUAAGGUCUUUUCUUAAAAAAAAAAUCCACCUCAUUUUCAGUUAACAUGUGCCAUUAAAUAGAUAACAUCCUGUGGAUUUAGGGAUAUUUUCCAGCCAGAAUGGAUCCAGAAGAAUUGAAUGGUGCUUAAAUUGAGAAAUAAUAAUAAAUAUAUCUAUAUAGAAUAGACAUAUCCCACUGUAUAUUAAUUGAGGUUACAGAAAGUUCUUUAUAUAAAACUUAUUUAAAUUUUUCAUAUUUCAUCUUUGAAAAAGUCUGAGAAAAAUCCAUAAUAUUUUCUGGUAUGAAAGUUUGACAGUAUUAAUAUUUUUUUUAUAUUUUCUUAAAUCAUUAAACCAUUUUAAUAUAUGUUAACUACUAAUAAAUGGUUUAUUCUUUCUAACUCCAUAUAAGCUUUUCCAGCAAAGAUUGUAAUAACACAUUUAUGUUCUCGUUUUUCUACAGAUAUAAGUAAAUUUAUAUAUAAAAAUACCAAAAAGAGGCUGGGCGUGGUGGCUCACGCCUGUAAUCCCAGCACUUUGGGAGGCCGAGGCAGGUGGAUCACCUAAGGUCAGGAGUUCGAGACCAGCCUGGCCAAUAUGGUGAAACCCCAUCUCUACUAAAAAUACAAAAAUUAGCCGGGUGUGGUGGCGUGCGCCUGUAGUCCCAGCUACUCGGGAGGCUGAAGCAGAAGAAUCGCUUGAACCCGGGAGGCGGAGGUUACAGUGAGCUGAGAUUGUGCCACUGCACUCCAGCCUGGGUGACAGAGUGAGAUUCCGUCUCAACAAGAAAAAAAAAAAAGAAUAUAUAUAUAUGUAUGUAUGUAUGUAUGUAAACACACACACUAAUUUGAGAGGACCCGUAGGGUGUCUGAGCCCAGCCACCUGAGUUUUUAGUACUGUGUUGUCAGGCUCUUCCCAGGCCUCAGGUGUUGUCUUUUGUGCUGUGUGGGGAUGCAUUGCUGCCUGUAUUUAUGAUCUUUUGCCGUGGUUCUGAGCAUUCACCUCACCAUGUUUACAAAGAACUGUUUUGUAUAUAGACAUUUUCAGGCACGUGCUUUGCACCAACCCUGCGUGGCUCUUGUCUGUGUUAGCUGUCACGGUGUGCACACUAAUCUCUGUUAAAGUUGUCUAUGGCUGUUCUACUUGUAAGAUAGUUUUCUAUUUCCUUCAGUAAUGUGUCCACAGUACCCUGUAUUUCGAGUUCCAUUAUACUGAAGUACUCAUGUUUUAAUAGUGCCUCUCCAAAGGCCUCACCUUGGACAGAGGUCAAUCCUUGAUGCUCCAGCACAGGUGACGUCACUAAUUGUCACUUUCCAGUUUGUUUUUCUCUAUUAAGGAAGACAUUUUCUAAUUGCAUCUCCAUGGGCUGUGAGACUGUGUGAAGCCGUUUGUGUGGUCUCCAUGUAGGUGCUGUGUUCCCGGCACCGCCUUGCUCUGAACACUGGUAAUUCCAGGUGCUGCGCUUGGCAGAGGGGUCUCGCCAAAGCGCAUGUGUGUGCAUGUGUGAACGUGUGUGUCCUUUGCAUGGUUGGGCGUGGGUGCCUUGCUAGGGCAUCAGCAGGACAUUGUGUGUAUAGUUACAAUGCUUCCAAACUGGAACUCUACAUUUUGUAUCUUUUAAAGCUCCUAUAAGUAAAAUAACUAUUGGCUUUAUUAAAAAUAUACAUUUAAUAAUA